AUGCACAUCGGAAACCUGCAUAUCAGUGAAGACAGCUCCAGGCGGGUUGUUGGGACCAUCGGCAUUCUUUUUCUGAAGUGCUGUGGCCUUCUGCUUGUGAUCAAAGGCAGUGAAGUAAUCAGAGAACUUUGUGGCAAAGCUCAUGAGGAAGGCAUGAUCUACGUUCUGCUUGGAGUAGAAUUCGCCAUGAAAGGCCUCAUCCCUGAUGCUCUCCACAGUGGGAGGCGGCGAGGGGGUGGGGAGCGGACCCUACACGUGCGCUACGUGCUGCGCCGGCCGCUGGGGAGCCCGGUCUGCCCCCCUCAUCCCAGAACCCGGUCCCAGGGCAGUUGCACGGCGCCCAGGGGGAGGGGAGGGAGGAAGUCCCCCCAAGUUUGCAACCCGGCAGCGUGGUCUUCGCAACGCGGUUACCGGAAGGAACGCGAGGAGCGCCUCAUCACCAGGCGGGUGUAUCUAGGGGCGAAGGCUGCAGAUCUGGGGCGCAGGCUGGAAAGUGGGGUGCAGCCGGUUGACGUGAGGUCUGGGAGUUGGAUGGACCGAAUGAGGAUGGAGACACCUAGGGAUGUGUCCGAAGGAUCUGGCGCUGCACAAAUGAGGGCGGUUUGGGGGACGGAGGCCCGGGCGGGGGCGGAGUGUUGUCCAAGAGUAAGGAGGGGGUUCCUGGAGACGUGGCACUCGGAGCGGGGCUGGGUUCCGCUCCGGCCGCCUGGGCUGCAGCUCCGCUAUGGCCUAGGAACCCGAACCUGACCCCGCCUAGGCCUCGCACCCAGCCCUCUGGGAGCUCCGGCCCCGGCACCUCCAGGCUGGGGUUGCCCAGGUCCGGCCUCUGGGGCGUCCAGCCGGCCCUAGACGAGACAAUGCGGCCCGGGCCCCGCCCCCGGAGGAUGACGCGCCCGGCUGCCGGCCAGUCAGCGCCCGUGGCUAGGCUCUUUAAAAAAAGAAGGGCCGGCGCGGUGUGGCUGUCAGCUGGGAGGGAUCCCUCCGCCCAUGUAAACAUCAUAAAGGGCAAGGGGAGCGUCUGUUGUGGGCGGGGGAGCGGCUGCCUUCCCGGAGAGUCCUCUCGGUCCCUAGGUUCCCCUCAAGACGCCGGCAACCGCCCCGUCCCUUAACGUCACACCGGGUCUGCUGGGAGCCAAACAGCUGCGGCCUGAUCUGGGAGCGAUAGAAUCUCAUCACUUAGGGUCACUACCGGAAAUGGAGGAAGCCGGACUGGGAGACCUUGAGAGUUGGGAGCGAGAGGGAAUCGUAGGACGCAGCUGAGAAUUGGGAAAGAUUUUCUUAGGCUUGUUCUUCCUGUCCAUCUCAGUUAAAUAAUAAUCAUAACUCAUGUAAGUCUAGAAUUUGUCUCAAAGUUAUGCCUACCUGGCUCGUAGGAUGCCAACGUUAGGAGUGAAAAUAGUCAACGCUCUCCCGAGAGAGCACAUGACACUACAUGAGCUUCAUCAAGACCCUCGGAGGCCCAGAAUGCGCACCAAAGAGCCAUCGACGAUAAUUCUUCUACCCAACUUUUAUUUAGUAUUAUUAAAUAUUCAGUAAAGUUAAAA